ACUCGGUCUGAGAGUUCGGAGCGCUGAGGUUCAGGCGCGCGCCUAACGGCUUAGCUGGGCUCACUCGGUCUGAGAGGUCGGAGUCUGCGAGUGUCGCUGCUGAAGGCUGUGGUGGACCGGGCUGGAUCGCGGAUUCUGAGCUACAUUGCGGGUUUGGGGGUGGAUCUUGGAUUUGGGGGUGGAUCGCGGGUUGCGGGGGGGAUCGCGGGUUGCGGGGGAGAUCGCGGAUUUGGGGCGGAGUGGGGGUGGAAAGGCCACGAGGAGCCGCCGCGGCUCAGGAGCGGGUGGUGGGCGUCUGAGAAGUCGCCACCAUGAGGAAGCUCUUCAGCUUCGGGAGACGCCUGGGCCAGGCGCUCCUGAGCUCCAUGGACCAAGAGUAUGCGGGUCCGGGUUACGACAUUCGGGACUGGGAACUGCGGAAGAUCCACAGGGCUGCCAUCAAGGGCGACGCCGCGGAGGUGGAGCGCUGCCUGACGCGCAGGUUCCGGGACUUGGACGCCCGCGACAGAAAAGACAGGACUGUUCUACAUUUGGCCUGUGCCCAUGGCCGUGUGCAAGUGGUCACUCUCUUGCUGCACAGAAGAUGCCAGAUCGACAUCUGUGACAGACUAAACAGGACACCUUUAAUGAAGGCUGUACACAGCCAGGAAGAGGCUUGUGCCAUCGUUCUCCUGGAAUGUGGCGCCAAUCCAAACAUUGAGGAUAUCUACGGCAACACUGCUCUCCAUUAUGCCGUGUAUAAUAAGGGGACUUCACUGGCAGAAAGACUGCUUUCCCACCAUGCAAAUAUUGAAGCACUAAACAAGGAGGGAAACACUCCACUUUUGUUUGCUAUAAAUUCCAGGAGACAGCAUAUGGUGGAAUUUUUAUUGAAGAACCAGGCAAAUAUACAUGCCGUUGACAAUUUCAAAAGAACAGCCCUCAUACUUGCAGUACAGCAUAACUUGUCAAGUAUCGUCACCCUCCUGCUUCAACAAAAUAUACGUAUCUCUUCUCAAGACAUGUUUGGCCAAACUGCCGAGGAUUAUGCUCUUUGUUCUGAUUUGAGAAGCAUCCGACAACAAAUUUUGGAACAUAAAAAUAAAAUGCUUAAAAAUCAUCUUCGAAAUGACAAUCAAGAAACAGCAGCUAUGAAGCCUGCAAAUUUGAAAAAAAGAAAAGAACGUGCAAAAGCAGAACACAACCUAAAAGUGGCUUCAGAGGAAAAGCAAGAAAGGCUCCAAAGAAGUGAAAAUAAACAGCCACAGGAUUCUCAAAGUUACGGAAAAAAGAAGGAUGCGAUGUAUGGAAAUUUUAUGUUGAAGAAAGACAUUGCCAUGCUCAAAGAGGAAUUAUAUGCAAUAAAAAAUGACAGUCUCAGAAAGGAAAAGAAAUAUAUUCAGGAAAUUAAAAGCAUUACAGAAAUAAAUGCUAACUUUGAAAAGAGUGUAAGACUCAAUGAAAAAAUGAUAACAAAAACAGUGGCCCGGUAUUCGCAACAGCUUAAUGAUCUGAAAGCUGAGAAUGCAAGGCUGAAUUCAGAAUUGGAGAAGGAAAAACACAACAAAGAAAGACUAGAAGCUGAAGUUGAAUCCCUCCAUUCUAGCCUGGCCACUGCUAUAAAUGAGUACAAUGAAAUUGUGGAAAGAAAAGACCUAGAACUAGUUUUAUGGAGAGCAGAUGAUGUUUCUAGACAUGAAAAAAUGGGUUCUAAUAUUUCUCAACUAACAGAUAAGAAUGAGUUGCUUACUGAACAGGUCCAUAAAGCUCGGGUGAAGUUCAAUACCUUAAAAGGUAAGCUCCGUGAGACAAGAGAUGCUCUCAGGGAAAAGACAUUGGCUUUAGGAAGUGUACAGCUGGACCUAAGGCAAGCACAGCAUCGAAUAAAGGAAAUGAAGCAGAUGCAUCCAAAUGGAGAAGCUAAAGAAAGUCAAUCCAUUGGAAAGCAGAACUCUUUAGAGGAGAGAAUACGUCAACAAGAACUUGAAAAUCUCUUGCUUGAACGACAACUAGAGGAUGCUCGUAAGGAAGGCGAUAAUAAAGAGAUAGUCAUUAAUAUCCACAGAGACUGUCUUGAGAAUGGAAAGGAAGAUCUUCUAGAAGAAAGAAAUAAGGAAUUAAUGAAAGAAUAUAAUUAUUUAAAAGAAAAACUGCUUCAGUGUGAAAAAGAAAAAGCAGAAAGAGAAGUGAUUGUGAGAGAAUUUCAAGAAGAACUGGUCGAUCACCUUAAAACAUUUUCAAUAUCAGAGUCUCCACUGGAAGGUACAUCACAUUGUCAUAUUAAUUUGAAUGAGACAUGGACUUCAAAGAAGAAAUUAUUUCAAGUAGAAAUUCAACCUGAAGAAAAACAUGAAGAAUUCAGAAAACUUUUUGAAUUAAUAUCAUUACUGAACUAUACUGCGGACCAAAUAAGAAAGAAAAAUCGUGAAUUAGAAGAAGAGGCAACUGGAUAUAAGAAAUGCCUAGAAAUGACAAUAAAUAUGUUAAAUGCAUUUGCAAAUGAGGACUUCAGUUGCCAUGGAGACUUAAAUACAGACCAACUGAAAAUGGAUAUUCUGUUUAAGAAGCUAAAACAGAAGUUUAAUGAUCUUGUGGCCGAGAAGGAAGCUGUGUCUUCAGAAUGUGUCAAUUUGGCCAAAGACAAUGAAGUUCUUCAUCAGGAGUUAUUAUCUAUGAGAAAUGUACAAGAGAAAUGUGAAAAACUUGAGAAGGAUAAAAAGAUGUUGGAAGAAGAAGUAUUAAAUCUUAAGACACAUAUGGAAAAAGAUAUGGUAGAACUUGGUAAACUACAAGAAUAUAAAUCGGAGCUGGAUGAAAGGGCAGUGCAGGAAAUAGAAAAAUUAGAAGAAAUCCAUUUACAGAAACAAGCAGAAUAUGAAAAACAAUUAGAGCAGUUAAACAAGGAUAAUACGGCUUCACUAAAAAAGAAGGAACUCACACUUAAAGAUGUGGAAUGUAAAUUCUCCAAAAUGAAAACUGCUUAUGAAGAGGUUACAACUGAAUUAGAAGAAUUUAAGGAAGCCUUUGCAGGAGCAGUGAAAGCUAACAAUUCCAUGUCAAAAAAAUUAAUGAAAUCGGAUAAGAAAAUAGCAGUGAUCAGCACCAAGCUCUUUACGGAGAAACAGCGGAUGAAAUAUUUUCUCAGCACUCUUCCUACAAGGCCAGAACCAGAGUUACCUUGUGUUGAAAAUCUUAAUAGUAUAGAACUCAACAGAAAAUAUAUUCCCAAAACGGCCAUAAGAAUUCCUACUUCAAACCCACAGACUUCAAAUAACUGCAAGAACUUCUUGACUGAGAUGGAGCUGGACCGUGUAGAACAAAUAAUUACAGGAACAAAGAAAAGUUUUGCUAUGUUGAGCACUUGCUCCCGUCUACUUUCUUUUGUAGAAUCCACUGCACCAAGGAAGCACAGGCGAGCCCUUCCCAUCAUGCGCUCACUAGUCCCCAACAGAAGAACCACUGUCGCAUCCACUGAGUUAGAGACACGCAGCAGUCUCUGUGAGUGGCUCUGCAUGAAGGAUUGUUUUCUAGGUGAAAGGCACAUCUCAACACAGCUGACUGAUCGGACUCAGCAAUUCCAUUCUGCAUCUCCUCUGGACACCCCCAGGACCACCAGGACAACCCCAUCAUGGCCCUGUCACCAGGCCCAGUCUCGCUCCGUGAUAACCAAGAUGCAGGUCCAGAGACAACCGCCCUACUUGGUUCCUGCAUCUGACCCCCCUUGGUGGGUAGUGACCAGCCCAACAUGGAAGAAGCCAGGGCAGCAUGCAGCCAGCUGCCCUGCAGCCCCAGAUGGCACCUGGGCCUUGGGAAGUCAUUCUCAAAGGGGAAGCUGGAAACUUUGAUGUCCCUGGAGGGAAGGGUGAACGUGGCAUCCGAACAACCCUGGCAGCCAGCAGCAUCUUGUCAUCCAACCUGUGGGACAGAGGCCCCCUGCUGGGGAGCGAGAUCCAUACCUAAAGGGUCCUGGCCCAGUUGGGCCUCAUCCUGGGCCCUGGGAGGGGAGGGGCACUAUGGUCCCCCCAGCAGCAGUCAGCAUUACCACCCAGGGGACUCAGCCUUCUGUGGCCCUGGCCAGAGUUAGAAUUUGGCCCAAGACAGGACAAGCUCACUCAGAGCAGGGUGUCAGUACCCAGGACCUGUGCAUGCCAGGCAAGGCCAAGCUGGCUCAAAGAGCAACCAGCCACCUCUGCAAGGGUGUGCCUGGAGCAAGUGGACCGGCCACCAACCUCACCCACUCAAGGAAUCAGGGGUGGCCAGGUUCCCACAGCCUGAGGGGCUGCCACUUGACGGCUGAUGGAGCAGAGGCCUGAGGAAAAGCAGAUGGCACUGGGGCCCUACCUCCAGGGCAGAAUAACUGAUUUACCCUGACUGGCAGCGAGUGAGGUUGGUGGCUGGUCCACCUGCUCCUGGCACACCCUUGCAGAGGUGGCUGGUUGCUCUUUGAGCCAGCUUGGCCUUGCCUGGCAUGCACAGGCCUCAAUGCAACCACUGUGCUGCAGAUGGAGCCACAUAGAGGAAAUGAGCAGCAGGCUCAGGAGCAGGCUGUGCGCUGCCUUUGGGGCUCCAGUCCAUGCAUGAGGGCUCCUACAGCACUGUGGGCUUCUUGGGUGCCAAGAGGCAGACCGCAGGCCAUCUUGAGAAGGACUCCAUGUUCAAGUGCAGAAAGGGCCCAAUCUCGUGGAUGAACCACAUGGCCAGCUUCUGGGUGCAGGCACAGUGCCACGUCUUCCAUCACUUCGUGAUGUGCCACACCAGCACUGAAGAGACAGCCUGGAGACAGGGCAAGAGGAAGGCUGCGAAGGAUGAGGUGGUGAAUUCCAGCUUCUUCCUGACCCUGAGCCCACCCCCAAGGUGGCCCUCAACCUUUAAGAGUGGGAGAGCAAAAUUGACGGCUUCGAGCGCUUCACCAAGAAGAUGGACCACAGGGCACUCAGCUCAACUUCUCAGCCAAUGAGUUGACAUGCAAGCAGAUUAUGGUGACGGGCUUUAAGAAAGAGCAUCAGAAGGUGGCCAGCUCUUCAGCCUCAGCCAGGUCUUGGAGCUGGACCAGGCCAUCACUUCACCAGAGAUGCCUUCAACACCGUCGGUGAGCUCUUUGCCAAUCAGCCCAGCCAGGAACUGGACCCAGUCAUGGACCUGUUAGUGCUGUCUCUGGGACACCAGGUCAUCAUCCUGGACAUCAUCCACAUACACAAGGAAGCUCUUACCAAAGUCAUGGAGAGCAGGCAACAUGUGGCAGAAGGGAAGACAGAGAUGCAGAGGCUGAUGACAUCAGAAUCACAGGAACAGGAUUUCUUUGGACACUGUGGCUGAAAUUCACCACUUCCAUCCAAUUCCAGUGAGAAACAUGGACUCACAGAUGCAGCAUUUCUUGCAACAAGAGAUACUAUUUUUUCAAAAGGUCACCCAGGAAUUGAUAGUGUUGAAUGACUAGAUACUCGAUUGUGCACUGUUUCCAGUUCAAGGAUGCUUUCUACAGCAGAAUAAUAACACUAGCAAAGAGAUAGUGCCAGGUAUUGGCGGUAGUACAAGGAUGGCUUUGUUCUCAAUUGAAACUCGGCUGAACAUAGAAUUGUGUAGGAAACAGUUAAUAUGGCGAUAGAAUAGAAACAGUAGCAAACAUGACCUAAACCAUGCUAUGAAUUCCUACACUACCAUUGUAACUUUUGGAAGAAUGAUACCACUUACUUUAUUGCUUUUUGAAGUAUGAAUAUUUUCGUGUAUAUGCUGUAGACCUCAAACCCUGUGAAGAGUCUCAAAGAAGCUGGCUGGAUAAAGCCUGCUGUGGAUGUCUUUAUAUUCAAAGAUUGAUGAUGCAAUUUGAAUAUGUGUCCUCACCAAAUCUCAUGUUGAAUUAUAUUUCCUAACGUUGAAGGUGGAUCCUGGUCUAAGGUGAUUGAAUCCUGAAGGCAAAUUUCUCAUGAAUGGUUCAGCACCAUCCCCUUGCUACUGUCCUCACAAUCAUGAGUGACUUCUCAUGACACCUGGUCAUUGAAAACUCUAUGUCACCUCCCUACUCUGCAUGUUUUCCUCUUGCCGUGUGAGACAACUGACUCUUUCUUUGCCUUGCACAAAGAUUGAAAGAUUUCUGAGGCCUCCCAGAAGCAGAAGCCCUGUGCUUCCUGUCCACCCUGCAGAACCGUGAGCCAAUUAAACCUCUUUUUCAUAAUGAAUCAUACAGAAAAUGGCAAAUGAGGACUGGAGCAUUGCUAUAAAGAUACCUGAAAAUGUGGAAGCAGCUUUGGAACUAGGUAAUGGACAGAGGUUGGAAGAGUUUGGAGGGCUCAAAAGAAGACAGAUGAGAAGGUUUGGACCAUCUUAGAGACUGGUUAAAUGGUUGUGACCAAAAUCCUGACAGAAACAUGGACAGUGAAGGCCAGGCUGAGGAGGUCUCAGAUAGAAAUAAGAAGCUUUCUGGAAAAUGUCUUCCUUUUGGAUAUGGAAAGCUUACACAAUGCCUGUACCACCACUGUACCUUAGAAGCAGUGAUCUUGCAUUUUAUUUCAGAGGCUUAUAGGCAAAAGAGGCUGCAGCCUUGACUCAGAUGAGACUUUGAACUUUGUAACUUUGAGUUAAUGCUGAAAUGAGUUAAGACUCAUGCUGGCAAGGCAUGAUUGUAUUUUGCAAUGUGAAAAGGACAAGAGAUUCAUGGGAUCAGGGACAGAA